GCGGUCUGGAGGCUCACGGGAGAGAGGCUGUAGCCCUGGGCAAUCCCGGGGGUCGUUACAGGAAGGUAGGAAAAUGCCACCCUCAGGGCACUGGUUGGGCUAAAGGUGACACUGGCGUCUCACGGGCUAUGAAGACGGAAUGCCUCUUAAUGCCGGAAUUCCAAGACGGAAUGCCUCUUAAUGCCGGGCAAGUCUCACAUGAAGCUACUCAUCAUUUGCUUCGUGUCCUCCGAGCUCCGAGAGUUGGCAAAGCUGAUGAAGGAGCAGUAGACAGCGACCCAAGCACACCACUUCAGCUAGGGAAAGACCGAUUUAAGGCUGCAAGGAAGGAGUCCUGGGAGCAUGGCUUUCCCUGAGCCAAAGCCGCGGCCUCCAGAGCUGCCGCAGAAACGGUUGAAGACGCUGGACUGCGGGCAGGGGGCAGUGCGAGCCGUACGAUUUAAUGUGGAUGGCAAUUACUGCCUGACGUGCGGCAGUGACAAGACGCUGAAGCUGUGGAACCCGCUUCGGGGGACGCUGCUGCGGACGUACAGCGGCCACGGCUACGAGGUGCUGGAUGCGGCCGGCUCCUUUGACAACAGUAGUCUCUGCUCCGGCGGCGGGGACAAGGCGGUGGUUCUGUGGGAUGUGGCAUCAGGGCAGGUCGUGCGCAAAUUCCGGGGCCACGCAGGGAAGGUGAACACGGUGCAGUUUAAUGAAGAGGCCACAGUUAUCCUGUCCGGCUCUAUUGAUUCCAGUAUCCGCUGUUGGGAUUGCCGCUCACGGAGGCCUGAGCCAGUGCAGACGCUGGAUGAGGCCAGAGAUGGCGUGUCCAGUGUGAAGGUGUCAGACCACGAGAUCCUGGCAGGCUCCGUGGAUGGCCGCGUGAGACGCUAUGACCUAAGGAUGGGGCAGCUCUUCUCAGACUACGUGGGCAGCCCCAUCACCUGCACCUGCUUCAGCCGGGAUGGGCAGUGCACCCUGGUGUCCAGCCUGGACUCCACAUUGCGGCUCCUGGACAAAGACACAGGGGAGCUGCUGGGCGAGUACAAGGGCCAUAAGAACCAGGAAUACAAGCUGGACUGCUGCCUGAGCGAGCGUGACACACAUGUGGUCAGCUGUUCUGAGGACGGGAAGGUGUUCUUCUGGGACCUGGUGGAGGGUGCGCUGGCUCUGGCCCUGCCUGUGGGUUCCGGUGUGGUGCAGUCGCUGGCCUACCACCCAACAGAGCCCUGCCUGCUGACCGCCAUGGGAGGCAGCGUCCAGUGCUGGCGAGAGGAGGCCUAUGAGGCAGAGGAUGGAGCAGGCUGAAGCCAGGGGACCCACCAACAGGACCAAGGACCGAGACACAGACAUGGAAGGACUUCAGAUACCAUCUUAUUCUAGAGACGUAGCUGACCAAAAAGUAGGGGAGGGGCUGGGUCUGCAAAUUAAUAAAUAGAAGAGGGGGUAAGACCUUCCUGGGACCGCA